AGCAAGAUCAUGUGUCAAAACAAACAAAAAAUUCCAAAUCAGCCAAACAAACCAAUCCUGGUUCUGCUAUUGACUGGCAGGGUGGCCGGGAGUGCAUCACUUGGCUUCCUCACCUGGCACCCCCCAUCUGUAAAUGGGUACACGGAUCCCCCCACACGGUGGCUAAGAGGGCUGACUGCAUUGUGGGUGCACGGAGCCCCCCACACGGUGGCUAAGAGGGCUGACUGCAUUGUGGGUGCACGGAGCCCCCCACACAGUGGCUAAGAGGGCUGACUGCAUUGAGAACCUGGCGCUUAGUAGGUGCUCACUGAUGAGUCACUGCUUCAGAGUCUUGUCUGAGCUCACACCACCACCCCUGGGUGCAUUUACCAUCCUCUGUCUGGAGCCUCAAAAAAUUAAAGUAAGAGGGGGAGGAUGAGUCUCUGAAAUGUCCCUUAUAAAGCAGCUCCAGGGGCAGCCAUGGUCUCCUGGGCUCUGCGCAGGGCCUGACUAUGGGCCCGCUGGUAUUUUUGCUCCGCUCGCUCGGCUCCCAGACACUGCUCUGCGGGAAAUGAUCCGCCCCCAUGUUUAUUUUGAGCAGCCCUGUCUGAGGUGGCGCUCGCAGAGAGAGGUGGCCCAGGGCUUCCAAGGGGGGUGCAGGGAGAGAAGGAGAGGAGGAGAGGGUGGGUGAACUCCCUCAGCCCUUCUCCUGCAGGGGAGGCAGCAUGGGGGGCCUUGCCCCAUACCCCAUCCUGGCUGGCAGGGAGCUCUGUGACACUGAGGGGCAGGAGGCGAGGGUGUGACAUCUGUGAAGUGGGGCAGAGUGACCUCAGGCCUGGUCACAGGGUGCUUGAAUGACAGGUUAGAUUGCAGUUGCUCAAGCCUUUAGGGUGACCACUGCUGCUGAAAUCUUGGGGGCAUUACCCAGAGAACAGCUUGCUCAUCCAGGUUCCUCAUGGCAGCAGAUGCUGUUUCUUGCAGGGCCUGGCCUAGAAGGAGGGGAUGGGUGAGGUAGGGUGUAGGCCAGGCAGGGGCCUGUGUGUGACUCACGAAGUGGUGAAAUGGGGCUGAAAUUCCCACCCCCUGGGUAGCCCAGGCUGUGUGACGGGCAGGUGGGACAGGUCAGCUGGGGUGGCCAGGCUUCUCCAGGGAGGCCUGAUUCCUUCAUCAUCACCGCCAUCACUGCAUCACAGCUCUUCCUGGUGUGAUCCUCUGGCAGUCUUGUGGGGCAGGCUGGGGGAGCAUCUAAUCACCACCAGGCAGAUGGGGAAACUGAGGCUCAGUGAAGUAGAUGGCUUGCCCAAGGUGCCAGGGUGAGCAGCGACAGAGCCGGGCUCCCGGAGAUUGAGGUCAGCUGUGGACAGUUGAACUGGAGGAAGGCAUUGCUCCUAGGAGCAGUGUCUGUUCAGCUUCUCUCUCCUGCACACACCCAUGCAGGCCCUGACUCCCCCUGAGCUGGGCAGGGCUGCCCUGCAGCUUUAUCAUGUCCUGGAGCUGGAGGCUAACCACCAAGUUGGAGAACAAAAAACAGAGGGUUGGGGCGCAUGGGCAGCAGGGCAGGGUGCGGGGAGCCUCCUGGGUAGGGCUGACCCCAGGCCAGGGCAUAGUUACUGGCCCCAGCUCCCAGAGGACUGCAUUCAAGGCCUCUGAAUCAGUGGCUGGAUCAAAGCUGGCUUUAUUCUUCCUUCAGCAGCCCCUUACGUGUCAAGUCACUGCCAAUCCAGGUCUGGGGUGACUCUGGGAAGUGAAGAAUGGGGUGGCUUAGUGGCUGACAUUCCAGCUCUAUAGGGGCCCAAGGGAGAGAAACACCAACAUGGACAGCAGUCAUGGAAGGCUUCCUGGAGGUGAUGGCACUGGGGACGGAUCCCGAAGGAUGACUAGGAGUUCAUCAGCGAGACAGAGGGACAGGGACCAGGAGCAUAGGUAUCCCCCAAAAGGACCCUGAGUCCUCAAGAAGGAUGUGUACAAGGGGCAGGGCAGACAGUGCAGGAGGCCAGGAGGGCUGUUCAUUCAGGAGGACCUUGGAGCUGGUUUUAUCCUUAGGGCAAUGGGGAGCCCGGAAAGGCUUGCAAGCAAAUGACACAUUUGUGCUGAACUGGGGCCUCAUCAGAAAAGGGGGGCAGGUGAAGGCACCUGGGCCAUGGAGGUGGGGAUGUGGCCAGAGGGAGAAGACCUAGGGUUGAGAUCUGACUUCAACACAGCCUGGCCAUGACCCUGGGCAGUCAGUUCCCUUUGAGUCUCAGGCUCCCUGUCUGUAAAAUGGUGAUAAUACAGGGCUUGAGAUUGAGAGGAGAUAAUGCAUGGGGCGUGCUCAGCACACCCGGCCCAUGGGAGGGGCCUAAUCAACGCUAGCUGCCAUUAUUAUGAUGGGGAUGGUGCUGGGCUGGAGGGCUUCCCGGGGGGCAGCUGACCUCUGCACACCCUUAUCUACCCCUACAGAAAUGGCAGAGGCUGGGCAGCCUGGUGUCACCCAAACCCGCAUCAGGCAGGGACUUGCAGGCUCCCACUGCUGCCCCCUACCUCCUGCCUCUGGCUGAACUUGGUGUUUUCAGCCCUUCAGCAUGUCUGCCUUCACUGGGUGGUCUUUGCCACCUCCAGCGAGCUUUCUGCCAUCUGUCUGUCUGUCCUGCUGUCUGUCUGCCUGCUCUUUUUGUGUCUCUUUCUGGCCGUACCUAUGGUUCCCAUGGUGUCACUGCUUCGUUGUCCUGGUCCUUCUUCACAUCCGUGUCCCUGCUUUCCUGUCUCCAUGUCUCCAUCUCUCCAUGCCCCACCUUUGCCCCUCACUCCCUUGUCUCUAUCUGUCUGUCUGUCUGUCUCUGCCCAUCUCCGCCCCUCCCUCUCCAUGUCCCCUCCUCCUUGGGCUCCCACUUGCUGUGUCUAUAUUCGUCUGUGUGUCUCUGUCCCGGAGAAAUGCUUUCAUGAGUGAUGGAUGGUCCAUUAGAAAAAGAUUAACAGGUGUGCUGAAUGGAGGAACAUCUGUUGUGAGGGAGGAGGAGGCGCGGGGUGACCUUUUGGAUGGCAGUGGCUCCCUGCAUCCCUGGUAGGAGUGUGUGCGUGGCGCGCGCGGCUGGAGCCAGCUGAUCAUCAUCACGGAGUGUCAGCGCCUACAGCUUUCAUCUCCGCGGACAUCGCUUACUGGGCUGGCAAAUUGCUGGCUCUGAGCAGCAUCUGGACCCUGGCUCAGUCCUCCCCACCGAGGGUCCCUCUCAGGGUCCUACUCCUCUUUUGGGACGACUUCUUGAGUCAGAUGUAAUUACAGAUGGAAAUGGGCCUUCUCCUUUCAUCUGGGCUUGAGAGGAGCUGGCAGUUUUAUUAGCUUUCCCAGGCAUCAGGCUGGAAGCUGGCGCUUGGGUUGUUAUUUUUUUUUUCCAUCCUCCUUUUAACCCACAUGGAGUCGGAGUCAGGUCCUUGCGGCUCCCCGUUGCUGAUGGAGGGGCUCCUGCUCUCGGUCCUCUGCUCUCCCACCUCCCAGCCAGCUGGGUCCUCCACCUGCACACCCUUCUCUGCUCCCUGGCGCCAGCUCUCUCUUAGCUUUUAGGUCUCUGCUGAGAUGUCGCUGCCUCCUGACCCCACUAGCACCGCUCCCCUAGCCACCCCCCACUUUCCUGGCGUCAGCACACACUGGCUUGGUUUGUUAACUUGGUUUACUGGGCUUUGGCCCCAGAGCACGAGCUUCUCAAAGGCAGGGACGGUGCCCUGACUCCCUCACCACUGCCCACCCUGGUAGCUCGAGCCCAGCACAUCAUGUCAUUCAAAUUUGUGGUAGCCAUGCAGGAAUGAAUGAAUGAAUGAAUGAAUGAAUGAAUUUGGCUGCAGUCCCCAUGUGGUGUAACGGGAGAGCAGUUUGGAGUCCAGCUUGGUUCAGUGCCCUGCCUUUGCCCUGCCACAUCCUUGCUAGGUGGCUCUGAACAAGUCAUUCCCCCUCCCAGUUUCCCUAGCCUCAGUCUCCUCAUCUGUAAAACGGAGAGGCUAACUUGUGUUGGGCGUCAAAUCAGGUCUCAACGACAGUGCUUCCUUUCUCUGUGAUUCAGGCAGGGAUGACCUGGCACCACAGUGAGCACACACCAGACACUUCAUCAGUCCCAGGGGAGCCGUGGCAGGGAGAGAAGGGGCUGGGCCUCGUAGGAGCCUUAGAGGAGAGGCUUGGAUGAAUUGGUUCCUCACUCGACCCCGUGGUUUUAUGGAUAAGGAAACUAAACUCCAGAGGAGGGGGGAAGCAACUUUCCCAGGACCACACAGCCACUUAAUGUCCAAACCAAACCCGGACCCCUCCAACUUCCCCCACUGCCCCCAGUCGUGGCCUCUAGUGUGGCCUGCUUUGAACACUGGGGUUCUUUGAACAAUGCCAUUUGCAGGAUAUCAGUUAAAAACCAGGGGUAAACAGCUCUGGGAGCAGAGGGAGGCUCCACAGCUGUUGGGGGAGGGAGCUAGUCUCCCUCUGACCAACUAGUGGCUUUGGGCAGGUCCUCUAACCUCCCUGGGUCUGAAUGUCCUCCUCCGAGAGCUGCUGGGAGUGCUAAGAGCCACCACGGGUGCUCUGUGUGCAGGACUGUGCCUGGCAUGCAGCAGGUACAUUGUGUCCACCGUCCUUUCAUGGGGCACGAUGUCCCCAGCCACCCUUGGUCCUGAGACGGCCAUUGCUGGGAAGGGGAGAGAAAAGUUCUGCAUGGGCGGGGGUUAAGGGCAGGAGUCUUGGAGCCAGGCUGCCUGGGUUCAAAUCCUGGCCACACCACUUGUUAGCUCUGUGGCCUCAGGCAAGGGACUGGCGUCCUGUGAACCCGUGUCCUUGCCUGUCUGCAGACGGGUUCUUGUGAGGGGCUAAGUGAAGUGAUGGCUGUAAAAUGCAUAGAACGGUUCCCGGCACGUGGUAAGUGCUCACUAAAUGGGUUAGUGACGUCUAGCGACGCCUGUCCUGCUUUCCUGUCUUGCUCUGCAUCUUAGCCGUGUGACCUCAGGCUGGCCUCCAAGCCUCUUUUUCCUCAUCCGUAAAAUGCGUAUCAGAACACUUCCCUGGUAGUGUGCUACAAGCCUCAUUUCCAAAUUUGUGGAAGGUCAGCGCUGUGGGGUCCCCCAACCCUCACCAUCUCAGCAGACCUCUCACGACCCCAAGGUAGCAGAGUUGAGAGGGGCCCUCGGGGCCUUGUGCAUGGGGCAGUGGGGAGACGGAGGUAUGGUGAGGACACCGACCUGCCAGGGUCACACAGCCAGGGUGGGUGUCCAGAGGGGAUCCACAGCUGCCCUCUGGCCUGACCGGGUCUCCAUUCCCCACCCCAAUGCCCCACAGCCGGAGGAGCUGACCAACAUCCUGGAGAUCUGCAAUGUGGUCUUCACCAGCAUGUUUGCCCUGGAGAUGAUCCUGAAGCUGGCUGCAUUUGGGCUCUUCGACUACCUGCGUAACCCCUACAACAUCUUCGACAGCAUCAUUGUCAUCAUCAGCAUCUGGGAGAUUGUGGGGCAGGCGGACGGUGGGCUGUCGGUGCUGCGGACCUUCCGGCUGCUGCGCGUGCUGAAACUGGUGCGCUUCAUGCCUGCCCUGCGGCGCCAGCUCGUGGUGCUCAUGAAGACCAUGGACAACGUGGCCACCUUCUGCAUGCUGCUCAUGCUCUUCAUCUUCAUCUUCAGCAUCCUUGGGAUGCAUAUUUUUGGCUGCAAGUUCAGCCUCCGCACGGACACUGGAGACACGGUGCCCGACAGGAAGAACUUCGACUCCCUGCUGUGGGCCAUCGUCACUGUGUUCCAGAUCCUCACCCAGGAGGACUGGAACGUCGUUCUCUACAAUGGCAUGGCCUCCACUUCUCCCUGGGCCUCCCUCUACUUUGUCGCCCUCAUGACCUUCGGCAACUAUGUGCUCUUCAACCUGCUGGUGGCCAUCCUGGUGGAGGGCUUCCAGGCGGAGGGUGACGCCAAUCGCUCCUACUCGGACGAGGACCAGAGCUCAUCCAACAUAGAAGAGUUUGAUAAGCUCCAGGAAGGCCUGGACAGCAGCGGAGAUCCCAAGCUCUGCCCAAUCCCCAUGACCCCCAAUGGGCACCUGGACCCCAGUCUCCCACUGGGUGGGCACCUAGGUCCUGCUGGGGCUGCGGGACCUGCCCCCCGACUCUCACUGCAGCCGGACCCCAUGCUGGUGGCCCUGGGCUCCCGAAAGAGCAGUGUCAUGUCUCUAGGGAGGAUGAGCUAUGACCAGCGCUCCCUGUCCAGCUCCCGGAGCUCCUACUACGGGCCAUGGGGCCGCAGCGCGGCCUGGGCCAGCCGUCGCUCCAGCUGGAACAGCCUCAAGCACAAGCCGCCGUCGGCGGAGCAUGAGUCCCUGCUCUCUGCGGAGCGCGGCGGCGGCGCCCGGGUCUGCGAGGUUGCCGCGGACGAGGGGCCGCCGCGGGCCGCACCCCUGCACACCCCACACGCCCACCACAUUCAUCACGGGCCCCAUCUGGCGCACCGCCACCGCCACCACCGCCGGACGCUGUCCCUCGACAACAGGGACUCGGUGGACCUGGCCGAGCUGGUGCCCGCGGUGGGCGCCCACCCCCGGGCCGCCUGGAGGGCGGCAGGCCCGGCCCCCGGGCAUGAGGACUGCAAUGGCAGGAUGCCCAGCAUCGCCAAAGACGUCUUCACCAAGAUGGGCGACCGCGGGGAUCGCGGGGAGGAUGAGGAGGAAAUCGACUACACCCUGUGCUUCCGCGUCCGCAAGAUGAUCGACGUCUAUAAGCCCGACUGGUGCGAGGUCCGCGAAGACUGGUCUGUCUACCUCUUCUCUCCCGAGAACAGGUUCCGGGUCCUGUGUCAGACCAUUAUUGCCCACAAACUCUUCGACUACGUCGUCCUGGCCUUCAUCUUUCUCAACUGCAUCACCAUCGCCCUGGAGCGGCCUCAGAUCGAGGCCGGCAGCACCGAACGCAUCUUUCUCACCGUGUCCAACUACAUCUUCACGGCCAUCUUCGUGGGCGAGAUGACAUUGAAGGUAGUCUCGCUGGGCCUGUACUUCGGCGAGCAGGCGUACCUACGCAGCAGCUGGAACGUGCUGGAUGGCUUUCUUGUCUUCGUGUCCAUCAUCGACAUCGUGGUGUCCCUGGCCUCAGCCGGGGGAGCCAAGAUCUUGGGGGUCCUCCGAGUCUUGCGGCUCCUGCGCACCCUACGCCCCCUGCGUGUCAUCAGCCGGGCGCCGGGCCUGAAGCUGGUGGUGGAGACACUCAUCUCCUCCCUCAAGCCCAUCGGCAACAUCGUGCUCAUCUGCUGUGCCUUCUUCAUCAUCUUUGGCAUCCUGGGAGUGCAGCUCUUCAAGGGCAAGUUCUACCACUGUCUGGGCGUGGACACCCGCAACAUCACCAACCGCUCGGACUGCAUGGCCGCCAACUACCGCUGGGUCCAUCACAAAUACAACUUCGACAACCUGGGCCAGGCUCUGAUGUCCCUCUUUGUCCUGGCAUCCAAGGAUGGUUGGGUGAACAUCAUGUACAAUGGACUGGAUGCUGUUGCUGUGGACCAGCAGCCUGUGACCAACCACAACCCCUGGAUGCUGCUGUACUUCAUCUCCUUCCUGCUCAUCGUCAGCUUCUUUGUGCUCAACAUGUUUGUGGGUGUCGUGGUGGAGAACUUCCACAAGUGCCGGCAGCACCAGGAGGCUGAAGAGGCACGGCGGCGUGAGGAGAAGCGGCUGCGGCGCCUGGAGAAGAAGCGCCGGAAGGCCCAGCGGCUGCCCUACUAUGCCACCUAUUGUCACACCCGGCUGCUCAUCCACUCCAUGUGCACCAGCCACUACCUGGACAUCUUCAUCACCUUCAUCAUCUGCCUCAACGUGGUCACCAUGUCCCUGGAGCACUACAAUCAGCCCACGUCCCUGGAGACAGCCCUCAAGUACUGCAACUAUAUGUUCACCACUGUCUUUGUGCUGGAGGCUGUGCUGAAGCUGGUGGCAUUUGGUCUGAGGCGCUUCUUCAAGGACCGAUGGAACCAGCUGGACCUGGCCAUUGUGCUACUGUCAGUCAUGGGCAUCACCCUGGAGGAGAUCGAGAUCAAUGCGGCCCUGCCCAUCAAUCCCACCAUCAUCCGCAUCAUGAGGGUUCUGCGCAUUGCCCGAGUGCUGAAGCUGUUGAAGAUGGCCACAGGAAUGCGGGCCCUGCUGGACACGGUGGUGCAAGCUUUGCCCCAGGUGGGCAACCUGGGCCUCCUCUUCAUGCUGCUCUUCUUCAUCUAUGCUGCUCUCGGGGUGGAGCUCUUUGGGAAGCUGGUCUGCAACGACGAGAACCCGUGCGAGGGCAUGAGCCGGCAUGCCACCUUCGAGAACUUCGGCAUGGCCUUCCUCACACUCUUCCAGGUCUCCACGGGUGACAACUGGAACGGGAUCAUGAAGGACACGCUGCGGGACUGCACCCACGACGAGCGCAGCUGCCUGAGCAGCCUGCAGUUUGUGUCGCCGCUGUACUUCGUGAGCUUCGUGCUCACCGCGCAGUUCGUGCUCAUCAACGUGGUGGUGGCUGUGCUCAUGAAGCACCUGGACGACAGCAACAAGGAGGCGCAGGAGGACGCCGAGAUGGAUGCCGAGCUCGAGCUGGAGAUGGCCCAUGGCCUGGGCCCUGGCCCGAGGCUGCCUACCGGCUCCCCGGGCGCCCCUGGCCGAGGGCCGGGAGGGGCGGGCGGCGGGGGCGACACCGAGGGCGGCUUGUGCCGGCGCUGCUACUCGCCUGCCCAGGAGAACCUGUGGCUGGACAGCGUCUCUUUAAUCAUCAAGGACUCCUUGGAGGGGGAGCUGACCAUCAUCGACAACCUGUCGGGCUCCAUCUUCCACCACUACUCCUCGCCUGCCGGCUGCAAGAAGUGUCACCACGACAAGCAAGAGGUGCAGCUGGCUGAGACGGAGGCCUUCUCCCUGAACUCAGACAGGUCCUCGUCCAUCCUGCUGGGUGACGACCUGAGUCUCGAGGACCCCACAGCCUGCCCACCUGGCCGCAAAGACAGCAAGGGUGAGCUGGACCCACCUGAGCCCAUGCGUGUGGGAGACCUGGGCGAAUGCUUCUUCCCCUUGUCCUCUACGGCCGUCUCGCCGGAUCCAGAGAACUUCCUGUGUGAGAUGGAGGAGAUCCCAUUCAACCCUGUCCGGUCCUGGCUGAAACAUGACAGCAGUCAAGCAGCACCCCCAAGUCCCUUCUCCCCGGAUGCCUCCAGCCCUCUCCUGCCCAUGCCAGCCGAGUUCUUCCACCCUGCAGUGUCUGCCAGCCAGAAAGGCCCAGAAAAGGGCACUGGCACUGGAACCCUCCCCAAGAUUGCGCUGCAGGGCUCCUGGGCAUCUCUGCGGUCACCAAGGGUCAACUGUACCCUCCUCCGGCAGGCCACCGGGAGCGACACGUCGCUGGACGCCAGCCCCAGCAGCUCCGCGGGCAGCCUGCAGACCACGCUCGAGGACAGCCUGACCCUGAGCGACAGCCCCCGGCGUGCCCUGGGGCCGCCCGCGCCUGCUCCAGGACCCCGGGCCGGCCUGUCCCCCGCCGCUCGCCGCCGCCUGAGCCUGCGCGGCCGGGGCCUCUUCAGCCUGCGGGGGCUGCGGGCGCAUCAGCGCAGCCACAGCAGCGGGGGCUCCACCAGCCCGGGCUGCACCCACCACGACUCCAUGGACCCCUCGGACGAGGAGGGCCGCGGUGGCGCGGGCGGCGGGGGCGCGGGCAGCGAGCACUCGGAGACCCUCAGCAGCCUCUCGCUCACCUCCCUCUUCUGCCCGCCGCCCCCGCCGCCAGCCCCCGGCCUCACGCCCGCCAGGAAGUUCAGCAGCACCAGCAGCCUGGCCGCCCCCGGCCGCCCCCACGCCGCCGCCCUGGCCCACGGCCUGGCCCGGAGCCCCUCGUGGGCCGCGGACCGCAGCAAGGACCCCCCCGGCCGGGCACCGCUGCCCAUGGGCCUGGGCCCCUUGGCGCCCCCGCCGCAACCGCUCCCCGGAGAGCUGGAGCCGGGAGACGCCGCCAGCAAGAGGAAGAGAUGAGGGUCGCAGGGGCCCCCGGCCGCCCACCGCCCGCCCCGUCUCACCUUCUUUACCUCAGGAGCCAGGAGCAGACAGCAAUACUUCGUCCACACCUGGGAUCGCGCAGGGCCCGCAGGGCACAGGCGCCCGACAGCCGGGCUGAGCGGAGUCUGGGUUAGCCAGGCCUGCGUGGCCCAUGGUGGCCCUUCCAGUGCAUAUACAUACAUAUAUAUAUAUAUAUGCAUAUAUAUAUAUAUAUAUAUAUAUAUGUGUAUACACACACACAUAGACAGACAUAUAUAUAUAUAUUUAUUUUUUUUACUGAGAGCUUAUGACUUCCAGAAAGUGCUAAAGGUGGGAGGUGGGCCAGGGCCUGGACGGGGCUUUUGUCUGAUGCUCUGGGAUUCUGGCCAGACCCACCCCAGGGCACAUGUCCUGCGGGGGCGUCCCAGCUGUGUUUUUUGAUGUCUCCUCCCUGGUUAAGAGUAGCUUGGAGAGGACCCUCAGGCCUCUGAGGGCACCAGGCCCUGGAGAAGAGGUGCAAUUCAGGGUGUGUGUGUGUUUUUUUUCCUUUAAAGAAGAAACGCUGCUAAGAUCCCACGUGGCUCCCACGUGUCGGGGUGUCUGUCCUGUCAUCCUGACUGUCUCGUUAUUGUGAAGUCUUUCGUAGACACCCCAGAGCACACACAUCCCCUUAGUCCACCGGUUAGAUGUCUCUCUUUAGAAAAAUCAGGGGUGAGUAGCUGUGUUUCCUUAGGCCUGGGGUAGGGGAUGGAGAGCAGCUCCAAGGCUGAGCUGGGGCUCUGGCCCCAGGUGAGGUCCCCAGCUCCUGAGCACUUCUGAGGGGGUGGGUUCCACCCCCAGGAGGGCGGGGGUGGGUGGAGCAGGAGUGGAGGCAGCCUGCAGAGGAAGGGUGCGGGAGACUGAGCCGGCAGUGGCUUGCUUGGAGGGGCUAGGGUACCCGCCUGGUCUCGGCUGGCUCCAGCUGCCCUGCAGGUGCCCCUGGGCUCAGGUAGUUAGUUGUUCAGCCACUAAUGCCUUUUAUCCCCCAUAUGGGCGCUGAGCUGUGGCUGUUCCUGGACACUGUGCUGUCCCCGUCCUGAGCAACUAUGCCCCCGCCCCAGUAGGUUCAAGGCAAAGCAGCUCUGACCGAAUUCUAGGCAGGGGUGGGGGCACCUGCCUGGGCCCUGGGUCCAGCCGCAUCCCCAUGCCCAGCCUUUCGCGUCACCUGGAGGCCACAUCUUCCCACCCCACCUGCCAGCCCCUGUCUCUCCUCCCCGCUGCCCCUAACUGCAGCUCAGCUUUCACUAUAGCAGUGCUUCCCAAACGGGUUCUAGACUUGGGUGUUUGAUUUGAAGAGUUACGCAUUUAUUUCACUAUUUAUUGGGAAAAAAAUGCAUUGAACCCGUGAUUUCACAGACAUUUUGCUUAGGUCAAGGCUACUUUUUAAAAAGGGAGUGACUUUCAUGAAGUCAGUUUGAAGAAGGAGGUUGGGAGCAUGUUGGUGGCAGUGAUCUGGAGAGGCUGCAGGGGCCACGAGUUUGCAGAUGCUGUACUUCAGCAAUAACCUUGCCUUUGCUAAGACCCCCUCCGAGGGCUUCAGGGGGGCCUGCCAAGGGGGGGCCUUGUUCUUGUUCCCAAACUCUGACUUGGAAGAACUCAGCUUGUGGCCGGGCUGGUGAGGGUGUGGGGUGCGCCCUUCCCUUUUGGGCUGAGGGAGAGGGGGCCGGGAGGGGUUGUCAAGCCCACCCGGGAAACUGAGCCCUGGAGAGGGGAAGCAGCCAGCCCAGGAUGCUUCAGGGCCCUGGCAGCAAAGAAGCUGGGGUGGUGUGGAGGGCCCUACUCCACACCCUAGAGCUGUGAUGCUGAGCAAGGUGCCUGUGGCGGAAGGAACUGCCCAGUCCUCCCUGGGGGCAGGUAGACCUGUGGGGAUGGCUCGGUCCAAGCCCAACACUGCCCGCUCCAGAGAGCCUCAGCCCUGCCUCCCUUUCCACAGAGGUGGUUUUAUGUGGAACGAGGUACCUUGUCUGGGGAAGAAGUGGAGCUGGGCAGGCUUGACUGCUCCUGGCUGACCCUGAGCUCUCGCAGUUGGAGGGAAGCAGACAGACUUGACUUUUUGCAAGUCCGCGUGUUGCUGGAGGGACACGUGUAUUGGAGCCCAGAAGAGGGGCUGUGUGGCCUGGGAAUACCAUGUGGAAGGUUGGGCUUCAAGUUAACAGGAUCAGACACCAGUCAAGCAGCCUCAGGUCAUCUUGCGACUCCACUGAGCAGCCUUUCCUGUUGUCACAUGGGUUCAGAGCAGCUGAGCAGGGAACACGUCCUAGGCAGGUCUGACGUGAAACCUCCCCUUACCCUGAACCGUGUGACUCUGCAAGCAGACACCUCGAGGCAGGUGUUCUAGGCAAAGGGAUGGGCAUGAGCGAAGGCUCCAGGGUCCACAGAGCAGGGAGUGUGGAGAAGGUGGAAGAGCUGAGCUCAGAGGCAGAGAAGCUCCUUGCAGGGAGCACUGGGAGAUGGCCUGGCCCGUCCCAGGCUCCUGGAGGCCCCACCUGCCGAUCCCAGGCACUUGACCUUGUUCCUGUGGGUGACAGAGAUGAGAACCAGGGAAGCUGUGAUCCACUGGCCAGGACAAGUCAACAUGGGUGAGGGUUGGGCAAAGGGCCCUUCCUUCCUCCCCAACCCUGUGGUCUGGGGCCAUGGCCUCAGGCUUGUGUCUAUCACAAAAGCACAAACUUGCCCUAACCCACAUGGGCCUGGCUGUGGGGAAAGUGGGGACCCAGGUCCCUGAGCUGUCUGCUGGGCUCCGUAGAGCGGUGGUGGGCAGGCACCUUGGCAUCUGUGCAGAGACGGCCCAGUCUGGCCAAAUCCUCUUCCUCUCCCCUGCUCUACCUUCUCCGGCACCAGGCAGCCCCUUAAAGGAGGACAAAGUGUGUAAAGCCCGUCUGCUGUCUUCCCCCAAAUCCUCAGCUCAGAGCCUUCCGCUUCCAGGGCCAACCCCAGCCCCGUUUGCUGCGUUGUGUAAGGGCUUGGGGUCUUAGAAGCUGCUCUUUAGCCCAGAUACACAUACUCUUUUUUGUCUUUGUGCAAUAAUCAGUGUUCCUGGCAGAGCCUGGGCCAAGCUGCAGCCUACUGAGGAGGCAGAGGCCACCUCCUCCAGAAAGCCCUCGGCCUGGGCCGCCGCCGUGACUCUAGCACUCUCAGUCGCUGUACAGUUUCUAUGGUGUGAAUGAACUUCCCUCCUAGUUGCUGAUGGCGCUGGUACCUGCUGGCCCAUGGCCCGGGUGUAGAGAAACCAAGCGGCAGCCACCACCAGUGUUGUUUUGAAUAAAAGCCCAGAAGCCUAUUUAAGAA